AGAGAUCGCGAGCGAGGCACCAGCCUGCAGCCGGCCCCCAGCACAUCCUCAGCCGCACAGACACUCGGCGAGGUGGAGGUGAGGGCGGGCGCCAGCGAACUCGGAGAGGGGCUCGCUCACUCCCAGGCGAUCCCAGCCGCCACCGCCGCCGCACCAGCAGCAGCAACAGCAGCAGCAGCUUCCUUCCUCAGACUCCCCUCGAGAGGCUGGCCAAGCGGGUGUAGCCGUUGGGGGAGGCUCCCGCCGGGGGAACCCGGCGAGGACAAGAGCAGGGCGGCCGCCUUCCACUCGGGCUGUCCGGCGGCGGCUGCCUCCGCCCGUGUGUCCGUCAAGGGUGCCGCGGGAUGUGUGUCAGUUUACGCCUCUGAGAUCACACAGCUGCCUGGGGGCCGUGUGAUGCCCAAGGCAAGUCUUGGUUUUAAUUAUUAUUAUUAUCAUUAUUGUUACGCUUGGCUUUCGGGAAAUACUCGUGAUAUUUGUAGGAUAAAGGAAAUGACACUUUGAGGAACUGGAGAGAACAUAUAUGCGUUUUGUUUUUAAGAGGAAAACCGUGUUCUCUUCCCGGCUUGUUCCCUCUUUGCUGAUUUCAGGAGCUACUCUCCUCCUGGUGAGGUGGAAAUUCCAGCAAGAAUAGAGGUGAAGACAAGCCACCAGGACUCAGGAGGGAAACGCUGACCAUUAGAAACCUCUGCAUAAGACGUUGUAAGGAGGAAAAUAAAAGAGAGAAAAACACAAAGAUUUAAACAAGAAACCUACGAACCCAGCUCUGGAAAGAGCCACCUUCUCCAAAAUGGAUAUGUUUCCUCUCACCUGGGUUUUCUUAGCCCUCUACUUUUCAAGACACCAAGUGAGAGGCCAACCAGACCCACCGUGCGGAGGUCGUUUGAAUUCCAAAGAUGCUGGCUAUAUCACCUCUCCCGGUUACCCCCAGGACUACCCCUCCCACCAGAACUGCGAGUGGAUUGUUUACGCCCCCGAACCCAACCAGAAGAUUGUCCUCAACUUCAACCCUCACUUUGAAAUCGAGAAGCACGACUGCAAGUAUGACUUUAUCGAGAUUCGGGAUGGGGACAGUGAAUCCGCAGACCUCCUGGGCAAACACUGUGGGAACAUCGCCCCGCCCACCAUCAUCUCCUCGGGCUCCAUGCUCUACAUCAAGUUCACCUCCGACUACGCCCGGCAGGGGGCAGGCUUCUCUCUGCGCUACGAGAUCUUCAAGACAGGCUCUGAAGAUUGCUCAAAAAACUUCACAAGCCCCAACGGGACCAUCGAAUCUCCUGGGUUUCCUGAGAAGUAUCCACACAACUUGGACUGCACCUUUACCAUCCUGGCCAAACCCAAGAUGGAGAUCAUCCUGCAGUUCCUGAUCUUUGACCUGGAGCAUGACCCUUUGCAGGUGGGAGAGGGGGACUGCAAGUACGAUUGGCUGGACAUCUGGGAUGGCAUUCCACAUGUUGGCCCCCUGAUUGGCAAGUACUGUGGGACCAAAACACCCUCUGAACUUCGUUCAUCGACGGGGAUCCUCUCCCUGACCUUUCACACGGACAUGGCGGUGGCCAAGGAUGGCUUCUCUGCGCGUUACUACCUGGUCCACCAAGAGCCACUAGAGAACUUUCAGUGCAAUGUUCCUCUGGGCAUGGAGUCUGGCCGGAUUGCUAAUGAACAGAUCAGUGCCUCAUCUACCUACUCUGAUGGGAGGUGGACCCCUCAACAAAGCCGGCUCCAUGGUGAUGACAAUGGCUGGACCCCCAACUUGGAUUCCAACAAGGAGUAUCUCCAGGUGGACCUGCGCUUUUUAACCAUGCUCACGGCCAUCGCAACACAGGGAGCGAUUUCCAGGGAAACACAGAAUGGCUACUAUGUCAAAUCCUACAAGCUGGAAGUCAGCACUAAUGGAGAGGACUGGAUGGUGUACCGGCAUGGCAAAAACCACAAGGUAUUUCAAGCCAACAACGAUGCAACUGAGGUGGUUCUGAACAAGCUCCACGCUCCACUGCUGACAAGGUUUGUUAGAAUCCGCCCUCAGACCUGGCACUCAGGUAUCGCCCUCCGGCUGGAGCUCUUCGGCUGCCGGGUCACAGAUGCUCCCUGCUCCAACAUGCUGGGGAUGCUCUCAGGCCUCAUUGCAGACUCCCAGAUCUCCGCCUCUUCCACCCAGGAAUACCUCUGGAGCCCCAGUGCAGCCCGCCUGGUUAGCAGCCGCUCGGGCUGGUUCCCUCGAAUCCCUCAGGCCCAGCCCGGUGAGGAGUGGCUUCAGGUAGAUCUGGGAACACCCAAGACAGUGAAAGGUGUCAUCAUCCAGGGAGCCCGCGGAGGAGACAGUAUCACUGCUGUGGAAGCCAGAGCAUUUGUGCGCAAGUUCAAAGUCUCCUACAGCCUAAACGGCAAGGACUGGGAAUACAUUCAGGACCCCAGGACCCAGCAGCCAAAGCUGUUCGAAGGGAACAUGCACUAUGACACCCCUGACAUCCGAAGGUUUGACCCCAUUCCGGCACAGUAUGUGCGGGUAUACCCGGAGAGGUGGUCGCCGGCGGGGAUUGGGAUGCGGCUGGAGGUGCUGGGCUGUGACUGGACAGACUCCAAGCCCACGGUAGAGACGCUGGGACCCACUGUGAAGAGCGAAGAGACAACCACCCCCUACCCCACCGAAGAGGAGGCCACAGAGUGUGGGGAGAACUGCAGCUUUGAGGAUGACAAAGAUUUGCAGCUCCCUUCGGGAUUCAAUUGCAACUUCGAUUUCCUCGAGGAGCCCUGUGGUUGGAUGUAUGACCAUGCCAAGUGGCUCCGGACCACCUGGGCCAGCAGCUCCAGCCCAAACGACCGGACGUUUCCAGAUGACAGGAAUUUCUUGCGGCUGCAGAGUGACAGCCAGAGAGAGGGCCAGUAUGCCCGGCUCAUCAGCCCCCCUGUCCACCUGCCCCGAAGCCCGGUGUGCAUGGAGUUCCAGUACCAGGCCACGGGCGGCCGCGGGGUGGCGCUGCAGGUGGUGCGGGAAGCCAGCCAGGAGAGCAAGUUGCUGUGGGUCAUCCGUGAGGACCAGGGCGGCGAGUGGAAGCACGGGCGGAUCAUCCUGCCCAGCUACGACAUGGAGUACCAGAUUGUGUUCGAGGGAGUGAUAGGGAAAGGACGUUCCGGAGAGAUUGCCAUUGAUGACAUUCGGAUAAGCACUGAUGUCCCACUGGAGAACUGCAUGGAACCCAUCUCGGCUUUUGCAGUGGACAUCCCAGGAAAAAAAAUAAGACUACACAAGAGGGGGAAAAAACAGCAGGUUUUCCUUGAAAUGCUCUGUUUUUCCCACCCUCAUGCCCUAAGAGAAGGUAGCCAACAAAAGAAAUGAAAAGAGCCAAUUGCUUGUUCACAUAUCUACUUACAACAAUGGAGAAUAGCUGAUUUUUCAAAGACUUGGGGUAAAAAAGAGGUUCUAGAAUUUUCUUUCAUCAGCUUUGCUGUGUUUUUCCAGUCUGCACAAUUGUGAAGCCUAUCUUUAUAGCCAAACAUGUCUCUGGCUGCAUUUUUCUUCUUUUCAUGCCAUUGUUGGGGCUCAUUGGAGACAUUCUGGCCUCAGCUGCUCAUCCGCCUCCACACUUGAAAGUAUUACUAGGUCAUUUCACAGUCUUCUUGUUUGCAGUCAGUAUUUCCAAUUCUUUUUAGUGUUUCCUUCUAGUUAUUCAACUAAAAAUAAUAGAAACGAAUGGCUAAAUUCAAGAUCAAACUCUUCCAGUAAUCUCACACCAAGCCCCCUCCUUUUUUUUCCGCACUUGAAACCAUUUGAAAAAUUCCAAAAAAUAUUUUUUCCAUGACCGUGCCUAGAUUUGGCUGUAGCCCAAGAGAUAAAAGCCUGUGAUAAAGGCUCUUCUGAUGGUGCUUCUAAACUCAAGCCAAACCCAGCAAGGAAUGAAUGGCUCUCAAGUAGCCCGACUUCUUAACAGAGGAGAUUUGGCAAAGUUUAGAUCAACACCUGAAUGUUUGGCUCCUUAUUGCAACUUGGAUGAACAAACUGAAUUGGGAAAUUAAGUGUGGUGGGGAAGGCGGACCUUCAGCCAAUACUAAAUAUUAAACUGAAUUAAACCGAAUUUUGAAGUGCCAAGAAGAAUCUCCUUAGUCCUUUGUUAUUUAUCUUUUACUGAGGUCUCAGUGUUGUAUUUCCUGCUGGGAUUAAAAGAGAAUGGCUGAGAGAAGUUUCUGGAGGCUACUCAUCUGAAAAAUCCAGCGAUUUAACUGGCCCAUGGGGUUCAGAAACUUGGAAUCAAGUUCAACAAAGGCACUAAGUGGCCAAGAGCUUAUCCCAAAUAAAUCACAGCCCCCAAACAAGGUGUUGAAAAUCUAUGGCUUACUCUCAGUUCUACUGCUGAUUUAUUCAAUGACUUAUUGCACUUCUCUACCCUCCCUCCUCAAUUUCAUCUCUAAAGUCAAAGUGAUGACACCUGGUACCUGUGAAAAUGAAUGAUUUCAGUGGUUUCCUGUGUGUAAGAGGCUCUUCGAUCCUUGCCUUCAAGGCUGGUUGAAAUGUGGUAGGUUAAGUGGAUGUGCUAAGACUGGCUUUCCAUGAGGUUUUCUCAGCCCAGCCUCAGUUAACACAGAGGCUUAAAACUAUAGGCACAAUUUACCCACUUUGUCAGUUCCUCAGUCACCAAUUAGCAGGACUAAGUCCUGAGCCAAACGGGCAAGUAUUGAACACAUAGAACCUCAUGGGUUCUCUUGACCUGUCCUUUUUGUGGUCUUCUCUUUCUGUGCACACCUUAAAACAAAUGGUUUCAGGGAGUGGCCACUCCCAGGAGAGGACAGAGUUAGGGUGAAGAAUGGGGCAGUGAGCAUCAUGGGGCAAUGGAGCCCUUUUGUUCAGAAGUUGCCUUGUCUCCCUCAACCAUCACCCUCUUCAAAGAACCCUCAUCAGAAAGGCCCUCGUACCUUUCUCAUUUCCUUCCUGUAAAGACAAGGGAAUUCUAGAGGAGAGGAGAGCAUCAGUGUUUACUUUACAGAGGAGCAAACAGAGACCCAGGGAGGUCAAUGACUGGUCAAGGCUCUGACACCUGAGGCAGAACCACAUGGGAGGUAGGCAUUCCGCCCCCAGCCUAGGGCCCUCCACAUCCCACGCCGCUUCCUUCAGUGCAGGGUGAUGCUGCCACUGACCAGGCUUCUGAGUGUCUCUGCUGUACACUCCAGAUGACAAGCCUGUCAUCAGCUUCAAGCAGACCUCUUAAUCCACUGCUCAGGGUUGGCAUGGAAGGGACUCUUCAAAGAAACCAGCACAUUAGUGACCUGAAAUGAUCUGUGUCCCAGGGCUGUCUUAAAUUAUUUACCCAAAAGUAACCAGUGGUUUGGGGCAGACUUCUCACUUUCCUGGCCAUAUUGUGAAGCUCCUUUACAAUGCGGGAAGUAAACAGUGUCGAGGCCAAUAUACUCAUACAAUAUGCUCUGUGUAGACACAGAGCGAAGGCUGAGAAUUUUCUGUAAGAAACUGCAGAAAAGCAAACUAAUGAAGGAAUGCUAAUCCCAAAUAAUCUUAACUUAGAAGAAGGAAGAAAAUGAGGGAGAGAGGAAAGAUAAAAAAAAGUGUCUGUGUGUGUGUGUGUGUGUGUGUGUGUGUGUGUGUGUCAGAGAAAGAGAGAGUGAGAAAGAAUGGAAAGGGCCAUAAGAGAGGGCCUUCUUAUUUGAGGACUAAAUCAUUCUCAGUAGGAAUUUCCAGGCAGCAGGUUGGAGUGUCUUGGGGGUGUUUCCCCUGAGCAGCAUGUGUGGUCUUACACUACCAGGCAGUGUUCCAGGGAAAAGCUUAUUUCAUUAGAAGAGGUUGGGUUUGUGACUGGAUAUGGCGUUCACCCUUUGUGCCGUAGUGUUGCAAUGUAUUGACAAGCACACUAGAGAAUAUUUGACUCUUCCAGGGUGGAGGGUGUUUCUGGAACAGUCUUGUGGGUGUUUUCAUAACUAGCCACCCUGGUCUCUCAUUCCAAAAAAUCAGGACAGCAGGAGAUCAGUGAGACCUUGAAUCAUGCCUCACCGUGUACCUACUCUGUCUCUCGAUGAUGCAGAGAGAAGGGACACUGACCAAAAUAAGGUGACUUUUUGGCCUGAGACUGAUCUUCAUAUGAAAAUGACCAGAGUUUUGUGAAGUUGGGUUGUAUUUGUUUUUAAGCAGUAGCUACUGUGCCCACUUGAUUACUCAAGCUCUGUAAAACCCCUUCCCAUCAUUCAUUCAGAGCUGACCUCUUUCUCUCACUGUGCUGAUCUGCAACAGCUGGGGAAGGGAUGGGUGUUGGAGAUCGGGAAGGCAGAGGUCUGACUCUCACAUAGAUAUAUGCAAGGUGGAAGAUUUGUGGCAAAGCUAGGUGAUCGCUUUGAAUUCCUUGAUGAGCCUGAUACGAAUGAAUGCAAGCCAAAAGACAAGAGAUCAGGUGCCAUGUUUGAAAGCAUUUCUAUCAAUCAGACAGAUAAAGGGAACAGAAAUCCCCCGAUGCCCAACUUGCAGCAGCCUCAAUUCCACAGUAUCCUCCUCUACACUCCCACAUUUUCCUUCCUGAUAGUGGCCCAGGCUCAUUUGCCCAAUCCCUGCCCUGGACUCCAGCAGCACUUGGGAGUCCUCUCCGCAAUGCCUCACUUUCUUUCAUGCUAAUUUGGCAUGGGUGAGUCUUCACUUCCCAACCACCCUGAAGGGCCUUGAUGGUAGACACCUGGUCCCUUACAUCUUUAUUUUCCAAAGUCAUCAGUUUGUUUCCUGGGCAUGCAGUGAGCCCUCUUACUAAGUGGUGUUAGGCUGGUUAGUUGGUUAAUGAAAACUGCCCUUUGAAGAACAAUGUAAUUUAGUUUCCUGCUCUGGGUGAUGCCUGUCAUGGAAAGCAUGAAACCCCAAAUUUCAGAUCCCCACUUCUUCAUGUUCAUGAGAAGCCCCUCAAAGCCCUACUCUAUCAAAGUAGUGAGCCAGUGAAACAGGCAACCAAAGUGUGUAUCCAGCCAAUCCGGAUCUGAGAUAAGGCAGACUCUUUUAUUUUAUUAGAAGGGGGCAGUAGGGAUAUGGUGGUAGUUACAGUGUCCCAGCCACACCCAAAGAACUUGAAUGCAGACUGGGGAUCCACCCUGGCCCUAAUACAGUUAUUUGAGAGUCAGUAUUUGUAGUCAGGCUGACCUGAGACUGAAUCCACAUGGGGGCCUAGAAGGAAACAGGGUCAUGGGAGCACAAAGGUUGAAAGCGGAACUCGUGUGGGUGGUAAGAUCCCUUCCUGACCUGCAUUCUUCUAGAGGUUUGGCCCAUUCCACUCUCCCUAGCCCAUCUCACACUCACCAACACACCCACCCACUAAAACAGAGUCCUGGAACUUCCUCUUCAAGUUUUCCCCAUUGAAAACAAAAUUCUGAGUCCCUGGUUCCUUUCUCCCACUCUCUCCUGAUGUCUGCCCUGACUUCGGCAGCUAGGUCUGCCAUCCUGUGGCUGCCAUUUCCCCUUUCCAGGGAGCUGUGGCCUCUACCCUCUGCCUUGGGCUCCUAGCUCAUCAUUCUCCCCUCUGCCUCCCAGAGGCCGGUAGCUUUACCCGUUGGUUCUCCUGGUAGCAUCUUACCUGCCACACCUUGCCUAUUCUUUGCUAGAACUACAGGGACCUAAUGAGAGAACCACAUUCCUUCCUGCUGGCCUCCUAAGGAAACAGGCUGCAGUUUACCUACCAGGCUCAACAGAAAAGGAAAGUGGCUGGUAAAGGGCAAAGAUGCUUUUGAGAGAGAGAAAGCUCUUAAUCAAACACAGAUAUCAAGAAUAUUAGCAAGGGGACUAGAGAAAAUUGCUAUCAAAGUAAAUGGUUUUUUGUACAAAUGUUCCCUUUAUUUGUGUUUUCCCCAGUGUGCCAUUCUUUCUUUAAGGCUUGGUGAACAGAUGUGCUUUUGAAAAUGUUGAUUAACUUAUCCUUUUUUUGACCCCCUUCCCACUCACUCAAACUCAGGGGAGCAGUGAUUAUAUAAAAAGCCAAGUCAAGCCACUAAAGUGUUCUUCUUCACCUUAAGUAGCCUUUGAUUCUCCAGGUGCAGAAAUCUCAGCUGCAUCUGGGCAAUUGAUUUCAUUGAGUCUUAGAAAUGGGCCAAUUCUUAGGAAAUCAUCUCAUCCAGUCCUCAACCUCCAGAGACAAGAGGCCGUGAUCUCCUGUGAUAAAAUGUUCUCAAAAUCAUUAGCAUCAUUUUACCCUUUUUCCUUUAAGAUCAAUGCCACAUUCACCCCUUUCCAGCCAGUGAUCUAUGGUAUCCUAAGACUUCUUCCCUGAGGGUGUGAGAUGGAGCAAGAUGGCAUUCUAGCCUCCAAGAAUUCAUCACAUCCUUGGCAGAAACAAGAUCCCUAAAAGCAAGCAUAGGAUUUGGCCCAGAAGUCACUGGCAGGAGCCCCGUGGUUCUCAUCCUAGGCUGAUUCACAUAUUCUUAUCCAGUGUUCUGCCUCUUUUACUGGUGAAGAUGUUAAGACAUAUGAGCAGCCCAUCAAACCAAUUAAUUGUUGGAAAUGUGACGGUUUUCUUCCAUGUUUUUUUUUUUUUUCAUAUGGAAAAAAACCCUGUGGGUUGACUUUCACAAGCUCGAUUUGAUCCCUGUGACAAACACCACCUUCCUCUUGUUGAUUCAUGUUCACAUCUCCCUUCCAAGGAAACAACCUGCUCUGUUGGGGCCUGGAGGAGAAUGCAGGGAAUGGGCGUUGAGGUGGGGAGGCUGGCGUGGCCUGCAGGUGCCACUUGCUGUGCUUUAAACAUGCAAGGAAUGGGCUGGAGUUAUGGAGGAUUAGUGCCAUGUGGCAUCAAUCUUUUAAGUGGGGUCUUGGCAAGUUGUUUUGUGCAUCCCUUACUAGGGACCGAGGGGGAUGAGAAUGUGCUUUAGCACUUUGGCCAGAAAUGAGAAAGACUUCUAACAUGAUUGAAACCAUGGCCUCCAGGAAAAGACUGAAUUUCAAAUGUGACAGUGAUGGAUCAAUGCUCAGUUCAGAUCAUGGUCAAGUAGAUCUUCCCCGAGAUGUAGUGCUGAUGAAGGAAGCUUUCGGGAUGGUCUAAAGUUCUUUUUCUCCCUCUUGUCUGAUACUUCAGCCGUUUGGGAUUUUGAUUUUCUUUUAAGCCUUGAUUUUUGGAUUUCAAUUUAUAGUAGUGACUUCAAGAUUGUUUAUCUGACUUGGUGGAACAAAACUCUGAGAGGGCCAUACACAUUCACUGGGGCUGUCUUGAGCUGACAGCUUGGAAAGGCAUAAUUAGCUUGUGAGAUAGGAAGAAAUGAUAAGAUGUUGCUCUUUGCCAUGCAUUUGAUGUUCUCUAUUAAUGUUUUACCAUUUUAGACAGAUAACUUUCAGUGGUUCUGAUUUCUAUAAGUUGGACAGCACAGUGAAUAGAGAGACCUGUAUUAUCACCCUCCCAAAUUAUCAUGAAAAA